CAGACAAAAUACCACGCUCACACCACACAUACCACAAGACAAAGAACAGGUAAAGAGGGCACACACACUUUUACCGUUUAUACCAAACCAAAAUCACGAAAUUCAAAAUCCGAGUACCAAAAAAUUCAAGCCAAGUCAAAACCAAAACCAAAGUAUCCAGCAAUUCAAGUCAAGUCAAAACCAGAACAAGAGUGCCCAUGCAGGCAUGCUGUGGGUGAUCAGGCCACGUUUCCACUCAGAUGGAGUGGGGCAAGUUCCAAAGACUAGUCUUACCAAGUCAAGCCAAGUCAAAACCAGAACAAAAGUGCCAAUACAGGCACACCGUGGGUGAUCAGGCCACGCUUCCACUCACGUGGAGUGGGGCAAGUUCCAAAGACUAGUCUUACCAAGUCAAGCCAAGUCAAAACCAGAACAAAGAUGUCAAUACAGGCACACCGUGGGUGAUCAGGCCAUGCUUCCACUCACAUGGAGUGGGGCAAGUUCCAAAAACUAGUCUUGACAAGCUUCAGAUGUCUGGACUUCAAGUGCCAGUUCCUUCCCGGUGUUCAGCCAGUGUUAAUCCUUCUCGGGAGCCUGCUAUGCGCUGCUCUGGCAAGGCAUUCCACCGGGGCCAUUUCCUACCCGGGAGCGCUCUUUGGAUUGCGUCAGUCAGGCUGGCCGGAGUCCUCUGCAGGGACGCUCCACAGGGCUUGUCAGUCACCUCGCUUCCUGGUCAGGGAACCAAGGACUGUAGCAGGACAAGCCACAGACAAAACCUCUCAGACACGGAGCUGUAGAAGAAAGGGCUUUAUUCAGCUGGGAGCAUUGGCAAGCUACUGCCUUAAAAUCCGAGCUCCCCGAGUGCACAAUUUCUGUCGCUUUUAAGAGCUCACAACACUAAAAUUUCACAUGAAAGGGUCGUGAUUGAUUUGAGCAAGCAAGGGGUACGUGACAGGGGCUGCAUGCACCGAUGGUCAGGGAGAAACAGAACAGGGCAGGGAGUUUCACAAUGUUCUUCUAUAGAAUGUCUGGAAUCUAUGAAUAACAUCGGUUUCUAAGUCAUGAGUUGAUUUUUAACUACUAGGUUUAGGCCAGGCAGGCCCAGGUCCAGUUUUGGGCCUGGCGCUGGGCUGCCUGUCUUUGAUUUCACUUCCUUUUUUUUUUAAAAAAAAAAAAAAAAACAGGUACUGAGUAUAAAACAAUAUGAGAGGGUCUCUCUCUUCCCUCGCUUUAACUUUCGGAGGGCUGAAAUUCUUUCUAGCCUUGGUUAAUACAGCAAUUCAUUCCAUUCUAGCUAUUGUUAUUUCUCUUACUAUAAUUUUACUAUUAGUACUUACGCUAUUCUAUUAUUUUCUUAAUUUUCCACUUAAUUAGGAUAACAAACCGAGGCCGGGCUCCCAUCCUCCUCAAGCACACGAGGGGGGCCUGGCCCAGCAGGGAGCUUCGCCUGGUUUCUGAGGGAAUUCCCGGCGGGCCUUUCCAAAACAUGCCCGUUCCCUUCCGCUAACUUCAGGGGCCAAGAAUUGAACUUUCACCCUCCUCAAGCCGGUGGCGCUGCCUCGCUGGCGUUCCCAGCGCGCAGCCAACCGGAUGCCAGCCGGCGGCAUUACCACUGCCAGCAUGGGGCGCCCGCGGACCUCCGACUGAGGCAGCUGCCGGGAGCCGGAAGUGUCCCGGGCGCCGGGACUGCGAGGGGGCCGGGAGUUCCCCAAGACCGGAAGUGUCCCGAGGCCGGGAGCCCGCGGGACCCCGGAGCGCGCGGGGCCGGAAGAGGCGGGCGGCCAGUGGAGGAAUCAAAGAUCAACUCCCACUGAGGACAAAUGGACCUGUAAUUCCGGGUGUGACGAGAGAACGAGAUUUACCUUCCUGAAUUAAAAAACAGGUCAUUAAGCUUGGGCCCUGACUCUUCUUUGUGAGAAGGUACAGAGAUGGAAACCUUACAAUCCGAGACUAAAACGAGGGUCCUUCCCUCAUGGCUGACAGCCCAGGUGGCUACAAAGAAUGUGGCACCAAUGAAGGCCCCCAAGAGGAUGAGAAUGGCAGCAGUGCCAGUGGCAGCAGCAAGACUCCCUGCGACAAGGACUGUGUACUGCAUGAAUGAGGCUGAGAUAGUUGAUGUUGCUCUGGGAAUCCUGAUUGAGAGCCGCAAACAGGAAAAGGCCUGCGAGCAGCCGGCCCUGGCGGGGGCUGAUAACCCAGAGCACUCCCCUCCCUGCUCCGUGUCGCCUCACACAAGUUCUGGGAGCAGCAGUGAGGAAGAGGACAGUGGGAAACAGGCACUGGCUCCAGGCCUCAGCCCUUCCCAGAGGCCGGGGGGUUCCAGCUCUGCCUGUAGCAGGAGCCCUGAGGAGGAGGAGGAAGAGGAUGUGCUGAAAUACGUCCGGGAGAUCUUUUUCAGCUAGGGCAUAAACUGUGCACUGAACUGUCUGCCGAGAGCAGCUGGAGGACAGCUGAGCUUCCACUGGUGCUGCUGGGCCGCCCGCCUGUGGGAAUGGGGCUCUCUGUGCUCCUACCUUUGUGCCUUCUUGGGCCUGGCAGAUUCACCUCAGGCCAGAAGCCCCUGGACACUCCGGGCCUUGGGGCUGCCGUUCUGAGUGUGCGGAAGGCAGGACUCAAAAUGAGAUCCCAUUUGACUCCCUCUGUAUGUACUGUGCCCUCUCCUGGCUCUUGAGGCUCUGGAGUCCCAAUUGUCUGUGUUAGUCAGUGACCAGGUUCCAGGGAAAAUGAUGUCAUGUGGUGGUCCAACUUACUGGAACCAAAGAGACAGUACUUUGCAAAGAAAAGGAUCACUGCCAGGUGCACUGGAAUUGCUACAGUUUAGUCCGCAUGAUCUCUCCUGAAGGAGGAAGCCUGUUUCAAAAAUAGUUUCCAUCAUGAGUCUAUCAAUGAGCUCCCACCUCUCCAGCCAGCCUAGAAAGCAAACGAGCUGCCCACAGUUCUCUGCCCUGUCUGGGAGGUUGAGGCCACAGUGUAUAGACUGGUAAGCCAGACAGGCCUCCUCCCGCAAGCUGCUACCUUGCUUUCACCUGUACCUUGGUCCCCGGGCAGCUAGCUAUAAAGCAAGAGGGACAGGAGCCCAGAAGAGACACUGAGGACAAGAGAUCACACCAGAGUACAUGUCUCUGCCUCUGUUUUCAGUGUGGCUUUGGACAGGAAUAUAUGAAUAAAUCACUGCCAUACAGGUUUUCCAAUACACAAGUGCUAGAAAAUACACACAAUUCCCCAAUG